UUCCCCCACCCACGUUCUAAAGCCAUCAGUGAGGGGCGCCUGCUCGAGUCCCCGCUGCCCAGGGUCGGGGACACUGAGGCGUUCGUGGGUGGGGCCCUUUUUUUGACACUGCGUGUGACGAGGUGUGGGAGAGCGUGACAGGCGGAGGAACCGGCGCGUGCAAAGGUUGAGGCGCGACUGAGCCAGGAGAAUUCGGAAAGCUGUUUUCUGCAGGGAACGAAGAAUAUGAGGCGGAGUUACUCCUAGGGUUGUACUGUCAUUGUGAGGAUGCUAGAAGCCACGGAGAGUUCUGAACAAAGGAGGGACGCCAUUUAUGUUAGUUUUUUUUUCUUUGAGACGGAGUUUCGCUCUUAUCGCCCAGGCUGGAGUGCAAUGACGCGAUCUCGGGUCACUGCAACCUCCGACUCCCGGGUUCAAGCGAUUCUCCUGCCUCAGCCUCCCCAGCAGCUGGGAUUACAAGCCUGCAGCUGGGAUUACAACGUCCGGCUAAUUUUUUGUAUUUUUAGUAGAGACGGGAUUUCACCAUUUUGGCCAGACUGGUCUGGAACUCCUGACAAGUGAUCCUCCUGCCUCGGCCUCCCAAAGUGCUGGGAUUACAGGCGUGAGCCACCGUGCCCGCCCUAUGUUAGGGUUUAAAAACUUUUCCAAAGACUGUUCACAGGAAGAGCAGCGAUGGGGCGAUGAGGACAUUGAGAUAGUGGGAGGCUACAUCUUUUUUUCAUUGCCCUACAGUUGGCAAGAGGUGACAGCACUGAGACCAGAAAGUAAAACAGCCAGCCUGAGUUCAGGGCCAGGCAGGGCUACAGGGAGGCUUGAGCUCAUCUAGCCUCACCAGGGAUGCAUUCCUCUUUCCCUGGUUCUCCCAGUUGUAGAAGGGCGUAUGGAACUCACAUAGGGAAGUGGAGAGUGUUCGGUCCCUCAGUAGCCUCUACCCCCAUGUUCUUGGGAUUGUGGUUUCCUAGUAUUCUUAAGUGCUGUUACCCCAAUCCUGGGUCUGGUGCCCUGGAGAAAUUCCAAGCCCAGGGCUCUUAAGUCCAUGCCAGAGGUUACAGGGGUUAUACUGAGGUGUUCCCAUUUUUGUCAGCCAGUGGAAACUUGUGAAAGGUUAUCUCUGGCACUGGUAUCAGGAGGCGCAAGUGCUUAGUAAAACUAAGCUGAGAUUUUUGAGGAAACCAUAGAUCUGUUUCCUUUUAGCUGGGAACAAAGAGCAGGGGGAAGGAGUCAGGACUGCAGUGGCUGCCUGAGAAGUUGGGUACCUAUUCUGGAGGUAAUGAGAGAUUUGGGUUACAAGAGGGAGGUGAUCUUACCAAAGUCCUAACAGGGUCCAUCCCGUUAGCGUGGAGAGCAGACUGUGGGGUUGAGGGAAGAGGAAAGAAGAUCAGAGUGGAAGCUACAGCCAGUCCAGGGUAAUGGACCAGAGUCAUUGAUUAGGAGAUGUGUUGCAUUCUGGAUGCAAAUUUUUAAAGGGAGCAACUAAAUUUUCUGAUGUAGACAGCGAGGGAGUGAAACAGGAUUCAGCGAUGACCCCAUGGUUCUUCAACUGAGAUGGAGAAGUUGGUAUUAACAGUAAUAUUCACUGGAGACAACAGGAGCUUUAUUUGGUCAUGUAAGAGUUUGAGAUGUUUCAGAGACAUUAAGUAGGCAUUAAGUAGGUGGCUGAACACCCAGGUCUGGAAAUCUGGGGAGUGCUUCAGAAUGGAGACAUCCAAAAUGUGGUGGUCAUUGUGUGGACUAAGGUGAGUGAGCUGUGGAUUACAUUUAGAAGGGUUGUUCUAUUUUUUUUUUUUUUUUUUGAGAUGGAGUGUCUCUCUUGUUGCCCAGGCCAGAGUGCAAUGGCGCGAGCUUGGCUCACCACAACCUCCGCCUCCCGGCUUCAAGCAAUUCUCCUGCCUCAGCCUCCCGAGUAGCUGGGAUUACAGGCAUGCGCCACCACGCCCGGCUAAUUUUGUAUUUAUUUAGUAGAGACAGGGUUUCUCCAUGUUGGUCAGGCUAGUCUUGAACUCCCAACCUCAGGUGAUCCACCCGCCUCAGCCACCCAGAGUUCUGGGAUUACAGGCGUAAGCCACCGCAUCCGGCCUACAAGGGUUAAUCUUUAGGCAUGGUGGUACAGGUUAUUUGGCCAGGAAGGGCAGAAUGGGGGCUAAGGACCAAGCCUUUUGGUUGGAUAAGUGGGUGAUAUUCUUGGGCUUUCUAAACAGAGGUAAGGGAGGUUAGUGGCUAUGGAGGUAGGGUGUUUGGAGAGGAUAGUUGGGCAGGUGGCAUACACUUUCAAGGGAAGAGUGGAUAUAAGGUGGAUGCAGAGGCAUAGGUGUAUUUGAGGCAAAUGGCUGUCCUUUUUUUCCUUUGUGCUUAUUCAGCACUCUGUGGAAUCACCAGGAUUUUUUGAUGACUUUGAUGGGGCCUAGGGUGUUUAUUCAACCUGGAGGAUAAGGCCAGGUGCCAAUGUGGUCAUCUGUGACAGUCACUUGGCCUGGGGUAGGUGAUCAGUGGAGCUAGUCUUUGAGUGUUAAGUGGACAGAGGAAGGUUGUUACUGCUGAGGGGCUAGCAAGUGCAGCACGGAAGUGGAAUAGGGCCAUGGGUAUCUGAGAUGCACAUGUGGUUCUGUGUGGCCUAAAUCUGAGGCAAAGAAUGGAGCCAGCCAGGGAGCCCUCAUAGGAUUUGGGGCUGCUACCACUAGUGGAUGCCCUGGGAGAUCUAGGGUAGUAUUAGAUCCGUUUGAAUCUGUCGAGCAUACUCUGGACGCUGUGUGCUAAGUUAUGGUGUAAAGUCUAAAAUUAAGGCCCAGUAUGACAUCUGGUGAAAUCAGGGUGGCAUCAAAUGGCCUGAGUACAAGUUUCCCUCCCUACUCUUCUCCCAAACAGACAACCCUUUUAAUCAAGGAGACCAGGCACAAUUUCUGCCUAUCACUUUGUAGCAGAUUUCAGCUCCCUACCAGGUCAUGGAGUUUUCCAAACAAGCCCAUUGUGGGAACCAGGGGGCAGUUGAUCCUUUUGUUCUCAAAGUGCUUGCAUCCCACAGUUUUUGGUUAUUCACUUUUUUUCUGGACUAGACCCCCAUGUGACCCUGUGUGGUACAUGUUGUCCUCAUCUCCCAGGUUCUAUGUACAUAUGAUUAAUAAACUGCUAUAUCAUCUUUCUUUUUUUUUUUUUUUUGAGACGGAGUCUCGCUCUGUCGCCCAGACUGGAGUGCAGUUUCGCAAUCUUGGCUCACUGCAACCUCCGCCUCCUGGGUUCAAGCAAUUCUCCUGCCUCAGCCUCCUGAGUAGCUGGGAUUACAGGUGUGCUUCACCACGCCCGGCUAAUUUUUGUAUUUUUAGUAGAGAUGGGGUUUCGCCAUAUUGGUCAGGCUGGUCUUGAACUCCUGACCUCGUGAUCCACCCGUCUUGGCCUCCCAAAGUGCUGGGAUUACAGGCAUGAGCCACCAUACCCAACUGCUGUAUCGUCUUUCUAGUGUCAGGUAUUGUGUGUUUGUCCAUAUCCAUAACCCUAGUGUGGCAAUCCUGCCUUCGCUAAUGGGGUAAAGAGGAAGAGAUUAAAACAGUGACAUGGGAGGUAAGAGCAGGGAGAUGCCUAUGGUGUGGGCAGUGAGGUGGCAGCCCUGGGCUUGGGGCUGUGGUGUCUGGAGAUAGGAGGGAUGUGUAUUCUGAAGAAUGAUGUGCAUCUGGAAAGGGAGUAAGUGACAGCUGCAGGGCCCUGGUAUUGAGACUUAGAUGACCUUGGACAUUUCAGGGGGAUUUCAUGAUGGGAUAGUAUGGAUCCUUCCAUGCCAGGCCCCCAGCUUAGAUGCCUAUUUAUCCAUGUGCUGGUUUCUCCUCUCAGUUGGGGAGCUUGGGAAGAGAAUGGGCAUGGGGUAAAGAUGUGGGGGUAUGCAUUGUGGGUCCUUGGGAUAGGGGCUCUUGGUGGUUUCAUCUGUUCCCAUUGUGGCAGGGCACUGUGACCUUUGAAGAUGUGGCCGUACACUUCUCCUGGGAGGAAUGGGGUCUCCUUGAUGAGGCUCAAAGAUGCCUGUACCGUGAUGUGAUGCUGGAGAACUUGGCUCUUUUAACCUCUCUAGAUGUUCAUCAUCAGAAGCAGCACCUUGGAGAAAAACAUUUCAGAAGCAAUGUGGGCAGAGCCUUGUUUGUGAAGACCUGCACAUUCCAUGUGUCAGGGGAGCCUUCCACCUGCAGAGAAGUUGGGAAGGACUUCCUGGCCAAGUUGGGAUUUCUCCAUCAACAGGCUGCUCACACUGGGGAGCAAUCAAAUAGCAAAAGCGACGGUGGGGCCAUCAGUCACAGAGGAAAAACUCAUUACAACUGUGGAGAACACACAAAAGCAUUCAGCGGUAAACACACACUUGUUCAGCAGCAGAGAACCCUCACUACAGAAAGAUGUUACAUAUGCAGUGAAUGUGGGAAAUCCUUUAGCAAAAGCUACAGUCUCAAUGACCAUUGGAGACUUCACACUGGAGAAAAGCCUUAUGAAUGUCGAGAGUGUGGGAAGUCCUUUAGGCAAAGCUCUAGUCUCAUUCAGCACCGGAGAGUUCACACUGCAGUACGACCUCAUGAAUGUGAUGAAUGUGGAAAAUUAUUUAGCAACAAGUCUAACCUCAUUAAACAUCGGAGAGUUCACACUGGGGAAAGGCCAUAUGAGUGCAGUGAAUGUGGGAAAUCCUUUAGCCAAAGGUCUGCACUCCUUCAACAUCGGGGAGUUCACACUGGGGAGAGGCCUUAUGAGUGCAGUGAAUGUGGGAAGUUUUUUACAUAUCAUUCCAGUCUCAUAAAACACCAGAAAGUUCACAGUGGAUCCAGGCCUUAUGAGUGCAGCGAAUGUGGGAAGUCAUUUAGCCAAAACUCUAGCCUCAUUGAACACCAUAGGGUUCACACUGGAGAAAGGCCUUAUAAGUGCAGCGAAUGUGGGAAAUCCUUUAGCCAAAGGUCUGCACUCCUUCAACAUCGGGGAGUUCACACUGGGGAGAGGCCUUAUGAGUGCAGUGAAUGUGGGAAGUUCUUUCCCUACAGCUCCAGUCUCCGAAAACACCAGAGAGUUCACACUGGAUCAAGACCCUAUGAGUGCAGUGAAUGUGGGAAAUCCUUUACUCAAAAUUCCGGCCUCAUUAAGCACAGGAGGGUUCACACUGGGGAGAAGCCUUAUGAGUGCACGGAAUGUGGGAAAUCCUUUAGCCAUAACUCCAGCCUUAUUAAACAUCAGAGAAUUCAUAGUCGAUAAAAGCCUUAUGAGUGGCAAAUGUGGAAAAUCUGUUAGCACCCUGGAGAAAGUCCUUGAGUACACAGUGAAUGUCAGAAAGCUUCAGCUGAAGGCCAUAUCUCAUUGAGUGCCACACAGUUCACAAGGGAAAGACACUUUUGAUAUGUAGGGAUGUCCAGUUGAUAUAACAGCUCUGAAGGAGAUCCCUUAUGAGGGUGGCAUCAGCCUGAAUUGAACAUCCUAUAUCUGAACAUCUGCAUAAAUUCCAGGUAUGUGUGAACUGCAUUGCACCUUUUGCCCUGCCCAGGGCCCAUGUCAGAUUUAUGUCUCUGCUGAUACUAUAGUGGAAGCCAUUUUACCUCUACUGCCUGGCAGGUGACCACCAGUGUGCACCACUCACCCAUCCCAGUGUAUUCAGGUAAGUGAACCUUGGUGUUCUGUUCAUGGGAGGAAUUUGUAAAUAGCCUAAGCAUUUAUUCCGUUUUUUUUUUUUCCUUUCUGAUGAGUUAGGCCAUGGACCUGACCCAGUUUGGCCCAGAGGACUCUGCUGGUGACCUGAAAAGAGGGACUACAUAUUUCAGGAUAUUGUUGGUCUCACAUGACUCUUGAUAGAGUUUGCCAGCCUUCAAAUCACCAACUGUGGGAACCAACUGCCUCUUAUUGCCUUGGUUUGUACAAUAACAAAGGCCUUAUUAAUCUUGGGGGUUCUAUAUGUAUGGGUUGGUUUGAAAACAGUUGGGUUCUGCUAACAUGAAGGGGUGAAUAACUUUUUUUGGAGAUCCCAAACAUUGUGUAGCUCAACAGGGACAGGGACAGGGACAGUAGGAUGGCAGAAUAUAGCUCUCUCUCUAGUUUGAGCCUAGUUUUCAUUGCUAUUCAAGGCCUCUGAGAAAAAACUACAGGGUAUUGUCCUAAUUUAUAUCCUGGAUGCCAUAGAGGUCAGCCUGAGGAGGCAGCAGUUACUUGACAUCCUUUGAUGUUUCUGAAAGCAACAUGAAAUUGUUCUCUUGUUCACAAGGAAUACUGCAUCGUGUUCAGUGCCAGUGGGGGAAAUCUGUUCCCCAGGUCCUGUAUGCCUUGAUAUCCUGAAUUCCACAGGGUAGCACCACAGGUGGUAAGAUUAUAGUAGGAAUUAUAAUUGUUAUAGAAGUACUGGAUUGAUAGAGAGUGGAAAACUGCAAUAACACUGCAAUAAAUAGAAUGUGCCCCUUUUACAGAGGUUUCCAUGAUGUUCGUUAUUAUGGCUCUUAAGGAUGAGCAGGUACAGAAAUCCUCAGGACCUACAGAAUUGUGUAUCUUGUGUAGCUGAGGUCAUUGUCAGAAAUUUUAUGGAAUCCUGUAGCCUCUGGGAUUUUCACCUCAAGGUCAUUGCUAUGCAGGCAGGAAAACAAGGAUAGAGAAGGGAGGUCUAGGCCAUUGAUACAGCCUUUGUGAUCCAGCCAACAUUUCUGUUGAGUCAGGUGGAAAUGGCCUUCACUGUUCACUUGUAUUUGUGAUCACUGAGGCAAAAUCCUCUCCCAGGACAUGAGGAGAGAGAUGGUGGAAUCAACAUAGGGUUGUCAAACCUGAUUUUCCAAAAACAAUAGGAAAUUCAGACUUUUAUUUUGAACCAUAUUUUGUUAGGUUGGUGCAAAAGUAACUGUGGUUUUGAACCAUGAUUUAUUUUUAUUUUUAUUUUUUUUUGAGUCAGAGUCUUGCUCUGUUGCCCAGUCUGGAGGGCAAUGGCACUAUCUCAGCUCAUUGCAACCUCCGCCUCCCAGGUUCAAGCGAUUCUUCUGCCUCAGCCUCCCAGGUAGCUGGGAUUACAGGCACCCGCCACCACGCCCAUCUGAGUUUUGCAUUUUUAGUAGACAUGGGGUUUCACCAUGUUGGCCAGGCUGGUCUUGAACUCCUGACUUCAUGUGAUCCACCCACCUUGGCCUCCCAAAGUGCUGGGAUUUACAGGCAUGAGCCACUGCGCCCAGCCAAGCUUUUUCACCAUUCCAAUUUCCUUCAAAUGCUGAACAGCCGUGGAAUGGUUGACAUUGAGUUCUUAGGCAACUUCUCAUGUAGUUGUAAGAGGAUCAGCUUCUAAUAUUGCUCUCAAUUGGUCAUUGUCAACUUCCAGUGGCUGGCCACUACUUCUCUUCAAGGCUCUUGUCUCCUUUGCAAAACUUCUUGAACCACCACUGCACUGUACAUUCGUUAGCAGUUCCUGGGCCAAAUGUGUUUAUAUCGUGAGUUGUCUCUGCUGCUUUACGACCCAUUGGGAACUCAAGUAAGAAAAUCUCAGCCGGGUGCGGUGGCUCACGCCUGUAAUCCCAGCACUUUGGGAGGCUGAAGUAGGUGGAUCACAAGGUCAGGAGUUAGAGACCAGCCUGACCAACAUAUUGAAACCUCAUCUCUACUAAAAAUACAAAAAUUAGCCGGGCGUGGUGGCAUGUGCCUGUAGUCCCAGCUACUUGGGAGGCUGAGGCAGGAGAAUCACUUGAACCCGGGAGGCAGAAGUCACAGUGAGCCAAGAUCACGCCACUGCACUCCAGCCUGGACGACAGACAAAACAAGACUCCGUCUCAAAAAAAAGAGGCCAGAUGCGGUGGCUUACACCUGUAAUCCCAGCACUUUGGGAGGCCGAGGUGGGUGGAUCACAGGUCACGAGUUCGAGACCAGCCUGGCCAACAUGGUGAAACCCCGUCUCUACUAAAAAUACAAAAAUUAGCUGGGCAUAGUGGCAUGCACCUGUAAUCCCAGCUACUGGGGAGCCUGAGGCACGAGAAUUGUUUGAACCCCGGGAGGUGGAGGUUGCAGUGAGCCAAGAUCAUGUCACUGCACUCCAGCCUGGGCAACAGAGCAAGACUCUAUCUCAAAAAAAUCGCUGAAAUUUGAGUUUUGUCUAACAUUUCCAUAGUCUAAAAUAAACAUAAACAGCAAGUAGUAAGUCAGCAAAAAAACAUAAAGCGAGAAAUGCCUAUUAAAAUGAUGUAUAACCACAUUUAUUUAAGAAUGUUUUCCAAUAUAAAAUGGCAAAAUCCAACAUGCAAAAACGGCAAUUACUUUUGCACUAACCUGAUAAUAAUUUUAAUAAGAAUAAAUGGUACAUAUUUAAACUAUAUAAUUUGAUCAGCUUUGAUAUUCAUAUUAACCUGUAAUUGCUCCCACCAUGCCAAUUUUGAAACUGCCAACAUGUUACUGAAUGUAGAAUUGGGAAGAGUUGCUGAUAGCAUCCUAAUAUAUUCUGUUUCUACCAUACUGAUACAGUGGCCACGAAUAACCUCAAGAAUGUAGAAAAUAAAAUGUAGUGAAAUGAUUAGGAAGAAGUUGUUUCUUCACAAUCAUGACAAUGAACGUGUCAUUCCACAAGUUACCUCAUUGUCCUUUAAUAAUUAUCUGCCUAUAGGCAACUAUUGAUUUACUUUCCAUUAUAAUACAUUAGUUUUCAUUUGCUAGAAUUUUAUAUGAUUGAAACCAUAAUGUAUUUACUCUUUUUUAAUCCCUGGGUAUAGUCACGUAUUUAUUUUGAGAUUCAUCAUUAUACCUCUAUGAGUAGUUUCUUUUUUUUGUAUUGCUGAGAAGUAUGAUGUUCUGUGGAUAUACCAGUAUUCGUUUAUUCAUUCAUUCAUUUGUUAUGGAUAUUUUGAGUAGUUUUUUAAAGUAGUUUGAGGUAUAAUGGAACUUAAAGUGCUUAUAUUUAAAAUGCAUAUUUUGAUAUUUUCAUACAUGCUUACACCCUGGAACGCAGUUUCCUUCUGUCUUUUUAGUUCAUUCUCAACAUAUAAAAUUAAUUUUCAUUGUGUAAAAUUACUGGUACAAUGACAUAUUUUGUCUCCUGUUACAGCUGUGUUCAAUUACAAAAAAAGAUGGAAAAGACUGUUAUGAAGCCAGAUGAACCUUUCUCCAGUCUUCCUUCACUAUUUUUUUUUCCUUCACCAUUUAUCAUUUCAUAGUCAUUUAUGUUUCAUCGGUCCUCAUGUGUACUAGUGCGUUAUUUUACUUAUACUCCCGGAUAUCAUAUUAUUUAAUGCAUAGCCUCUUCAGAAUGCAAUUUUAAAAUGUAAAGGCUCUUUUAUAACCCCCCAAAAAAUCACACAAAUAUAUUUUAAAAUGUAAAUAUUUUAUCGCUUCUGUUUUCUCAGUUGUCUAAAACAAUGUGUUUCUUAAGGAAGAUCAUUUUUAUUCAGGAUCCAAAUGUAUAUUUAAUAGCUUUCAGUAGUUGUAUCUCAUAAGUCUGUAACCUACAGGUUCCAUUUACCUUUGUUUUCUUAUUUCUUGAAGUUGCUGAGUCAUUUUUUAAUUAGAAUUUGCUGUAUUCUAGAUGUGGCUUAUUGAAUCUCUAACAUUGUUUAACUUGUACACUAGAUGUUGAUGAAAUCGGUGAUUGAGAUUUUGUCCCAGCAGACAGGUGUGUGAUGGCAACAGUGAAAUAAAUACAAAACCUUCUCCCAACCCAGAAAUCCUCUCCACGAAGGUAGAGACAGAAAACGCUUUUAUUAAGCAUUAAACCAGAAUGUGAUGCACAUCACAGACAAUCCACUAAGAAAUUGCAAGGUAAGAAAAAAGCCUCACUCCUUCAUAUGGCCUAGCAGAUGUAGCCCAUUACACACGUUUUCAAGAUAAACAACAACAAGUCCUCAAAUACGAAUUUGACAGCACCAUUUGUCACACAUAGUUCAUCCUAACAGGUGAUGCUCUAUUACCUUACUGGCUUUACCUAGAGGAAAAGCAAACAUCAUAUCUUUAUGACAGAGGAUAAUGAGGGGAGCUGCCUUGGGGCUGCUGGAUGAUACAUCGGGACAGGACAGUGCGAGCUUCCAGCAAGGCAGCUCUAGUUGGAGCCCUGAUUUCUUUCCAAGGUGAGGAGAGGGUGAUGAUAGUAUCCUUGGGAAGGGGAGUGAAAAGUGCUGAGGGACUGUAUUUAUAGCUGAGGGAUUUCCUGGGUGCUGUGGGUCUCUUGUCUUUGCCACUCUGCCUCAACACUGAAACUGUCCAUUCCCUACUUGGAGGCUGCACCCAAAACCUCCCUCUGCCUUCAUGCUCUGGCCUCCCCCUGCAAGUUACCACCCUGGGUCUUGGUGCUUGCAGCACUUCCGGUGCCUGGCUGCCCCAGGCCCUCUGCUCCCUCUGCUGCCUGGGUUUAAUCCCUCCUCUGCCACUGCCCAGCAUCAGGACUCUGCUGGUUUUGCAGCCUCUUGGUACCUCAGUUUUAUGUUUGUGGAAUAGGAGUGCUCACAGUACUCUCUGGGAUCCUGGCAAAAGGUGUGGUAGGCAGGUGGUAAGCAGGGCCGAGCACUAUCCCCAGCACCUAGUGAGUUGAUGCCUUAUCAUUUACCUGAUCCAGGCAGGUCUUAAGGUACAAGAGAAAGAGAAAUGGGGCUUCUUAGAACCCCCUGACCCCACAGCUUCUA